GCUUUUGCUGGACGUCAUCCUCGGGAGCCCACCCGGACGAAGGGGGAGAGUAGACAGCAGAACCAGCGGCGGCGGCUAAGCAGAGACUGUAGUAGCGGCGACAGCGACGACGGCAGCGAUGGCUGGGGCGGGGCCAGCCCCGGGACUCCCGGGUGCAGGAGGACCCGUGGUCCCGGGUCCUGGCGCUGGCAUCCCGGGCAAAAGCGGCGAGGAACGCUUGAAGGAAAUGGAGGCGGAGAUGGCCCUGUUUGAGCAGGAAGUUCUGGGGGCUCCAGUACCUGGAAUCCCAACUGCUGUGCCUGCGGUGCCCACUGUCCCCACGGUCCCCACAGUAGAAGCGAUGCAGGUCCCAGCGGCUCCUGUGAUCCGCCCAAUUAUCGCGACCAACACAUACCAGCAGGUCCAGCAGACUCUGGAGGCCCGAGCAGCUGCUGCAGCCACAGUAGUUCCUCCCAUGGUGGGUGGCCCUCCUUUUGUAGGCCCUGUUGGCUUUGGCCCUGGUGAUCGGAGUCACCUGGACAGCCCAGAGGCUCGAGAAGCCAUGUUCCUGCGGCGGGCAGCUGUGGCCCCCCAGAGGGCCCCUAUCCUGCGUCCAGCCUUCGUCCCCCACGUGCUACAGAGAGCAGAUUCCGCUCUCUCCUCUGCAGCAGCCGGCCCCCGCCCUAUGGCCCUACGGCCCCCUCACCAGGCCCUCGUGGGCCCCCCUCUGCCUGGGCCCCCUGGACCACCCAUGAUGCUGCCACCAAUGGCUCGGGCUCCAGGGCCCCCGCUGGGCUCCAUGGCUGCACUGAGGCCCCCUCUGGAAGAGCCAGCAGCACCCCGAGAGCUGGGCCUAGGCCUGGGGUUGGGCCUGAAAGAGAAGGAAGAGGCAGUGGUGGCGGCGGCGGCUGGGCUGGAGGAGGCUAGCGCGGCUGUGGCCGUGGGGGCAGGAGGUGCCCCAGCUGGCCCUGCAGUCAUUGGGCCCAGCCUGCCGCUGGCCCUGGCCAUGCCAUUGCCCGAGCCUGAGCCCCUGCCCCUCCCGUUGGAGGUCGUCCGCGGCCUCCUGCCCCCGCUGCGCAUUCCUGAACUCCUGUCCCUGCGUCCUCGGCCCCGGCCCCCUCGGCCAGAGCCACCCCCAGGCCUCAUGGCUCUUGAGGUCCCAGAGCCCCUGGGUGAAGACAAGAAGAAGGGGAAGCCAGAGAAAUUGAAACGGUGCAUUCGCACAGCGGCAGGGAGCAGCUGGGAGGACCCCAGCCUGCUGGAGUGGGAUGCAGAUGACUUCCGGAUCUUCUGUGGGGAUCUGGGCAAUGAGGUGAACGAUGACAUCUUGGCACGCGCCUUCAGCCGCUUCCCAUCCUUCCUUAAGGCCAAGGUGAUCCGUGACAAGCGCACAGGCAAGACCAAGGGCUACGGCUUCGUCAGCUUCAAGGACCCCAGCGACUACGUGCGCGCCAUGCGUGAGAUGAAUGGGAAGUAUGUGGGCUCGCGCCCCAUCAAGCUUCGCAAGAGCAUGUGGAAGGACCGGAAUCUGGACGUGGUCCGCAAGAAGCAGAAGGAAAAGAAGAAGCUGGGCCUGAGAUAGGGUCUGUGGCCAGGCACCCGCUCCCACCUGGCCGGGCGCUGGCUCCUCCCUCAGUUCUCUUUGGAAAACCCCCAGCUGUCCACCCAUCCCCUGCCCCAAAACCAGUUUCAAUAAAUUUACGUUCAUUUCCA